GUCAGAAGGCUGGGCAGCCAUGGCGUCCUAUUUCGAUGAACACGACUGCGAGCCGUCGGACCCUGAGCAGGAGACGCGAACCAACAUGCUGCUGGAGCUCGCAAGGUCACUUUUCAAUAGGAUGGACUUUGAAGACUUGGGGUUGGUAGUAGAUUGGGACCACCACCUGCCUCCACCAGCUGCCAAGACUGUGGUUGAGAACCUCCCCAGGACAGUCAUCAGAGGCUCUCAGGCUGCUCUCACCGUGCCCUGGGCCCAGUACUCAAGCUUCUUUCUGUUCAUGGACUGCUGGGGGAUGGAAGAAGAGUGGCAGUUGGGAGCAGGGGAGGGUGGUUAUCAGCUUAUGAAGAUCAGACCAAGGCUAGAACACUACUCUACUUUUCUCAGACAAAUUCCUGUCCCUUGUGCCGCUAUGAGCUGCCCACUGAUGACGACACUUAUGAGGAGCACAGACGAGAUAAGGCUCGAAAACAGCAGCAGCAACACCGACUGGAGAACCUCCAUGGAGCCAUGUACACGUGAGGAGGUUGGGGCUGAGUGCUGGCCCUCUGCGUCUUCCUUAUUAACCUUGAAUCCUCAUUAAAGGUUUCUUUACCCACCCUGAGGCUGUAUUGAUCACAGACCUGGCCAGGGGCUCUGCAUCCUCCAUCAGGUCUCUACUUCUGUUGGGGAAGGUGAUCCUAAAUCGCAGAAGGCACCAGGCUGCGGUUUUCCUCCCUGCUGGCC